AUUGCUGCAGACGCUCACCCCAGACACUCACUGCACCGGAGUGAGCGCGACCAUCAUGUCCAUGCUCGUGGUCUUUCUCUUGCUGUGGGGUGUCACCUGGGGCCCAGUGACAGAAGCAGCCAUAUUUUAUGAGACGCAGCCCAGCCUGUGGGCAGAGUCCGAAUCACUGCUGAAACCCUUGGCCAAUGUGACGCUGACGUGCCAGGCCCACCUGGAGACUCCAGACUUCCAGCUGUUCAAGAAUGGGGUGGCCCAGGAGCCUGUGCACCUUGACUCACCUGCCAUCAAGCACCAGUUCCUGCUGACGGGUGACACCCAGGGCCGCUACCGCUGCCGCUCGGGCUUGUCCACAGGAUGGACCCAGCUGAGCAAGCUCCUGGAGCUGACAGGGCCAAAGUCCUUGCCUGCUCCCUGGCUCUCGAUGGCGCCAGUGUCCUGGAUCACCCCCGGCCUGAAAACAACAGCAGUGUGCCGAGGUGUGCUGCGGGGUGUGACUUUUCUGCUGAGGCGGGAGGGCGACCAUGAGUUUCUGGAGGUGCCUGAGGCCCAGGAGGAUGUGGAGGCCACCUUUCCAGUCCAUCAGCCUGGCAACUACAGCUGCAGCUACCGGACCGAUGGGGAAGGCGCCCUCUCUGAGCCCAGCGCUACUGUGACCAUUGAGGAGCUCGCUGCACCACCACCGCCUGUGCUGAUGCACCAUGGAGAGUCCUCCCAGGUCCUGCACCCUGGCAACAAGGUGACCCUCACCUGCGUGGCUCCCCUGAGUGGAGUGGACUUCCAGCUACGGCGCGGGGAGAAAGAGCUGCUGGUACCCAGGAGCAGCACCAGCCCAGAUCGCAUCUUCUUUCACCUGAACGCGGUGGCCCUGGGGGAUGGAGGUCACUACACCUGCCGCUACCGGCUGCAUGACAACCAAAACGGCUGGUCCGGGGACAGCGCGCCGGUCGAGCUGAUUCUGAGCGAUGAGACGCUGCCCGCGCCGGAGUUCUCCCCGGAGCCGGAGUCCGGCAGGGCCUUGCGGCUGCGGUGCCUGGCGCCCCUGGAGGGCGCGCGCUUCGCCCUGGUGCGCGAGGACAGGGGCGGGCGCCGCGUGCACCGUUUCCAGAGCCCCGCUGGGACCGAGGCGCUCUUCGAGCUGCACAACAUUUCCGUGGCUGACUCCGCCAACUACAGCUGCGUCUACGUGGACCUGAAGCCGCCUUUCGGGGGCUCCGCGCCCAGCGAGCGCUUGGAGCUGCACGUGGACGGACCCCCUCCCAGGCCUCAGCUCCGGGCGACGUGGAGUGGGGCGGUCCUGGCGGGCCGAGAUGCCGUCCUGCGCUGCGAGGGACCCAUCCCCGACGUCACCUUCGAGCUGCUGCGCGAGGGCGAGACGAAGGCCGUGAAGACGGUCCGCACCCCCGGGGCCGCGGCGAACCUCGAGCUGAUCUUCGUGGGGCCCCAGCACGCCGGCAACUACAGGUGCCGCUACCGCUCCUGGGUGCCCCACACCUUCGAAUCGGAGCUCAGCGACCCUGUGGAGCUCCUGGUGGCAGAAAGCUGAUGCAGCCGCGGGCCCAGGGUGCUGUUGGUGUCCUCAGAAGUGCCGGGGAUUCUGGACUGGCUCCCUCCCCUCCUGUUGCAGCACAAGGCCGGGGUCUCUGGGGGGCUGGAGAAGCCUCCCUCAUUCCUCCCAGGAAUUAAUAAAUGUGAAGAGAGGCUCUGUUUAAAAUGUCUUUGGACUCCCAGGGCUGAGUGGGCUGGGAUCUCGUGUCCUCAAAGUGGAUGGGUUCUGGGGUGGCUCCUGAGGUAGAGGAGUGGAGAACUGGCUCUUAAGAGCACAGUUUUCUUUUCUUUUUUCUUUUUUGAGACAGGGUCUCACACUGUCACCCAGGCUGGAGUGCAGUGUUGCAGUCCGGCUCACUGCAGUUUUGACCUCCCAGGCUCAAGCGAUCCUCCUGCCUCAGCCUCCCAAGUAGCUGGGAGCCUGGGCAUGCAUCGCCACGUCUGGCUAAUUAUUAUUUUUUGUAGACAGGGUCUCACUGUGUUGCCCAAGCUUGUCUUGAACUCCUGGCCUUAAGUGAUCCUCCCACCUCAGCCUCCUGAGUAGCUGGGACUACAGGCAUGAGCCACCAUGCCUGGCCAACUCACAUUUUUCUUUCUAUUAUUUAUUUUUUGUAGAGAUGAGUCUCACUAUGUUGCCCAGGCUGGUCUUGAACUCUUGGGCUCAAGUGAUCCUCCCGCCUCAGCCUCCCAAAGUGUUGGGAUUACAGGUGUGAGCCACAGCACCUGGCCAACCAACACUUCUCAGGGCCUCUUUCAUCUGUGCUCUUCCAGGAUGCUGCCUCUUACUCCCUGGGCACCUCGGCCUGGUCCCAGCAGGUAUGGGCAGUUGCUUGAGGCUCCAGACAUACUCACCUCUACCUCGACCACAUCAACCCCAUCACCAAGAGGAGGUUCAGGGAAGCUGCAUUUUGUGGUCUUGUCCUCCCAGUCCAGGGUGGUAGUGCUGGGCUGUUCCCAGCCUCCCACAGCAGAGCUGGACGCUGUGGAAAUGGCUGGAUUCCUCUGUGUUCUUUCCCAUUAUCCCUCAGCUCUGAGUCCUCUUGUGCCAUCUGACAUCUGAUGCCUUCCCAACCACUGCCGAGUUUCUGCCUGGAGCAGGGCCUCAAGGCCCUGGCACACAGAAGAUGCGUAUCAGUAUUAUCAACCAAUAGUUGAUGAAUUGUGUUUUUCAACGAAUUUGCUAGUGAUCUGGUUUACUGCCUUAGUAAUAUCUAGUUCCUAAUAUGCCUAUGCCUUUUAAUGUCUGCACAGUCUAUGAUGAUGUCACUUCUCUCAAGCCUGAUGUGUCCUCUCUCUCUUUCUUGCUAGUGGUUUAUCAAUUUUUAAAACCUUUUCUUGUUUAUUUGUUUUUGAGACAGAAUUUUGCUCUUGUUGCCCAGGCUGGAGUGCAAUGGCGUGAUCUUGGCUCACAGCAACCUCUACCUCCUGGGUUCAAGUGAUUCUCGUGCCUCAGCCUCCUGAGUAGCUGGGCUGACAGGCACCCACCACCACACCCAGCUAAUUUUUAUGUUUUUAGUAGAGAUGGGGUUUCACCUUGUUGGGUGGCCAGGCUGGUCUCCAACUCCUGAGCUCAAGUGAUCCACCCGCCUCAGCCUCCCAAAGUGCUGGGAUUACAGGGGUGAGCCACCACGCCCAGCCCCAGCUUAGUUUUUUAAAAAGUUUAUUUUAGCCAUUCUAAUAGGUAUGUAGACAUAUCUAAUAGUGGUUUUCCUUGCGUUUCCUUAAUGUCUGAUGAUGUUAAGCAUUUUUUCCCCAAGUGCUUAGUUGCCAUCUAUAUAGCAUCUUUGAUGAAAUGUCUGUUUAUAUAUUUUGCACACUUUAAAAUAUUGGGUUGUUU